GGGCUGGGCUGGGCUCCGCGGCUGGAGCCGGGCUCUACCCAGAGCAAGACCCUGAUGGCUGCGGUGUUUCUGGUAACGCUUUAUGAAUACUCGCCGCUUUUCUACAUCGCGGUGGUCUUUACCUGCUUCAUCGUGACCACCGGCCUGGUAUUGGGAUGGUUUGGUUGGGAUGUUCCAGUAAUUCUGAGAAAUUCAGAAGAGACCCAGUUCAGCACAAGAGUUUUCAAAAAGCAAAUGAGACAAGUCAAGAAUCCUUUUGGCUUAGAGAUCACUAAUCCAUCUUCAGCUUCAAUUACAACUGGCAUAACCUUGACAACAGAUUGCCUUGAAGAUAGCCUCCUUACAUGCUACUGGGGGUGCAGUGUUCAAAAAUUAUAUGAAGCUCUGCAGAAGCAUGUUUAUUGCUUCAGAAUAAGCACUCCCCAAGCAUUAGAAGAUGCUCUGUAUAGUGAAUAUCUCUAUCAGGAACAGUAUUUUAUUAAAAAGGAUAGCAAAGAAGAAAUAUAUUGCCAGUUACCAAGAGAUACUAAAAUUGAAGACUUUGGUACAGUACCCAGAUCUCGCUAUCCAUUGGUAGCGCUAUUGACCUUAGCUGAUGAGGAUGACCGGGAAAUUUAUGAUAUUAUUUCCAUGGUGUCAGUGAUUCAUAUUCCUGAUAGGACUUAUAAACUAUCCUGCAGAAUAUUGUAUCAAUAUUUACUCUUGGCUCAAGGUCAAUUUCAUGAUCUUAAGCAACUUUUCAUGUCUGCAAAUAAUAAUUUCACUCCCUCCAACAAUUCCUCUUCAGAAGAAAAAAACACAGACAGAAGUUUGUUGGAAAAGGUGGGACUCUCUGAAAGUGAAGUUGAGCCAUCGGAAGAGAACAGCAAGGACUGUGUUGUUUGCCAGAAUGGGACUGUGAACUGGGUACUCUUACCAUGCAGACACACAUGCCUGUGUGAUGGCUGUGUGAAGUAUUUUCAGCAGUGCCCAAUGUGCAGGCAGUUUGUUCAGGAAUCUUUUGCACUUUGCAGUCAAAAAGAGCAAGAUAAAGACAAACCGAAGACUCUUUGAAGACAUCGUAACACUGAAAAGUACACUUUCUACUAAAGAUGCAGAAAUUGAUGAUCUUGGAAUUCAUCAUAACAUGGAAUCUACAGUACUGACCAUCAAUGAAAAUUAUAUUUUAACUUCAUAUUUGUAUGGUACUUGGAUGAUAAAAAUUAAUUAUUCCUUUCUGCUUAGUGAAUGAAUACUGGAAUCCAUCUGUGUUGAUACAUAAAAAUUCAUUCAACUCUUGAAAAGAAUCUAAGAGUUUGGCCUUUUAUUAGCUAGAUUUCCUCUCAUGUUAAUUAGAAAAAUCAUUCUGAAAGGCAAUCCAUUGAAAAUUUGAGGAGGUUAAAUUCUUAAGAUCACUAAAUGUUUUACCUUUGAUGUAAUCGGAGUGCAAUUAAGAAAAAACUUAAUUCUACUUAAAGUAAUUGUGUGUUCCCUAGUUUAUACAAAGGAGUUGGAAUGAGCUUCUUUAGAUCUUUUCCUGAAAUAACAGCUUUUAUAAAUAUCCAUCUGUUUGGUUUCUAAUGUCCCUUAUUAUAGUUACGUAAAUACAGGUCAUAGUUUUAAAUAUAGGUUCUUAAAUCAUAAAUACAAGAUAUAAUUCUUGACUGUUCUCCGUGUAUUAUAAAAUGAUACUCAUCUAUAGGAGGCAGAUAUAUAAAAUUCGGAUAAUAAGAUUUUUUGGAUAAUUAAAUUUAUUAAAUUGAUAGUCAAGUGUGAUUAGAUUAGCAGAAUGUGAUCUCCAGGGAAGAUCUGUGAGACCUUUAAUGCCUUACCUUAGAUUUCUGCCUGCACAGCAAAUCCAUCCAGAACUGAGGUGGGAGGUGGAGGUUAUAGAGCUAGAAAAAUCACUAAAAGAAACAAAUAACUAUUUUUUUCUAGUGUAUUUUUAUUCCAAAUAAACCCUGUAUUCUUCUGAAUAGUAAA